GGCUGCAGUGAGCCAUGAUCCUGCCACUGCACUCCAUCCUGGACAACAGUGAGACCUUGUCUCCCCCCACCCCCAAAACAUGCAAAUUGGGACAUCAAAUUGUUAAUGGUGUUUACAAUGAACAGUGCCUUCAGGUAGCUGCAGCUACUCUACAUAGAUUUGCAAGUUUUUGUAGUGAUAGGCUAUGGUAGAUGUUACCAGCCAAGGAGUGGCUGACAAACUCCUUUCACUGUUAUUUCAUUGUCAUGUUAAAAUUCAUAUUUUCCGUCAAAAUAGUGAUAGCUAGGAUUAUAAUCUAGGUCUUCUAAUCUUAGUAACGUGUUGUCUAUGUUAGGGCCUCUCAAAGUUGUAAAAAAGCUGUAUAGAUGUGUUACCAUCAAUCGAUUUCAUUUGUUUUUAUCCUAGUGUUAAAGGUACAAGUUUUUUUUUUUUUUUCUUUCCUGAGGCGGACUUUCACUCUUGUCGCCCAAGCUGGAGUGCAAUGGUGCGUUCUUGGCUCACUGCAUCCUCCGCCUCUCGGGUUCAGGUGAUUCUCCUGCCUCAGCCUCCCGAGUAGCUGGGAUUACAGGUGCCCUCCACCACACCUGGCUAAUUUUUUUUUUUUUUGUAUUUUUAGUAGAGUUGGGAUUUCACCAUGUUGGCCAGGCUGGUCUUGAACUCCUGACCGCAGGUGAUUCGCCCGCCUCGGCCUCCCAAAGUGCUGGGAUUGCAGGCGUGAGCCACGGCGUACCUGGCCAAAGGUACAAGUUUUAAAUAUGCUUUUAUCAUGCAUACAGUACUCUUAUAGAUUCUGUCAGAUUUAGGGAUAUUCUUUUCAGAUUGAUAAAUUGCACAAAAAUCUUGGAGUAUAUUCUUGUAAUUUCUUCUACAAAAUUCUCAAAACAACCUUUUUCCAAUGGGGAGAAGACAUGAACACUGAAGUCAUGUUUUUGGAAAAUACCUUGUUAAAAACAGACACUGCUGUAAGGGUUUCCUUGCUUAUGCUCUUUUGUAGAACUUUAUUGAUGUGAAGAGUUCUCCUUUUUCUGUAAAAGCUUAUUUUAGAGUACGAAGUAAAUGAGGCACUCAGAGAGUUAACCUCAUCAGGUCUGAGUUUAGUUCAGUUUAAACUUUUUGCUCUUAUGCUGGUUGAUAUCUUUGUAACUACUCUACUUCUAGAGUUAUUUUGAUUGGAAAAUGAAUUCCUUUUUUAGAACAUGGAAUUGUAAGGUAGAAAACUGCUAGGUUCUCAAAAGAAGGGAGAUAAAUUCCAACUUGAAAGUUUUUUCCCCUAACGUUCUAAUGCUUUGUUUUUCCUGUGUGUAAAUGCCUUCCUUAGGAACAAGGAAAAUUAUUAACUCAGCUGUGUUUCCUUCCCUUCUCUUUCUCACUGCCCCCCCGCCACCCCAUACCUUAAUACCUUUUGUCCCUUCAAUGCCUUUAUAAACUCUGUCUUCUCAUAGUUUUUCUGGUGAAGCUGUCAUGGCUCCUAUUUCAACCAUAAAGGAUUUGCAGUUCAGUGAUGCUACUGGUUUUACAUCUUCUUUCCCAUCAACCCCAUUGCCCUGGUUAGGAGACCUAGACCAUGGAGUACAUUGCAAUAUUGAAAGUAUUUCAUGUUUAACACAAUUUUUUUUUUUUUUUUUGAGACCGAGUCUCGUUCUGUUGCCCAGGCUGGAGCGCACUGGCACGAUCACGGCUCACUGCAACCUCUGCCUCCAGGGUUUAAGCGAUUCCCCUGCCUCAGCCUCCUGAGUAGCUGGGACUACAUACAGGUGCGUGCCACCACGCCCGGCUAAUUUUUGUACUUUAGUACAAAUUGGGUUUCACUGUGUUGGCCAGGCUGGUCUUGAACUUCUGACCUCAAGUGACCCAUCUGCCUUGGCCUCCCAGAGUGCUGGGAUUACAGGCGUGAGCCACUGCGCCCGGCCAUGUUUAACACAAAUUUGAAAGCGUACUGCUUAGUUUUUUAGGGGGAGUAUGAUAAUCAUAGAGAUGAGACUUGAUCUUUGCUGAAAGUGUUCUUUAUGAAGUCUGAUGUGCAUAAAUUUGCCCAAUAAAAUGCUCUUUUAUUUACACAAAUCAUUUUAGUCGCACUGUAGCCAGAGUGUGGCAUAGCCUGAUGGCUGGCCUCUUUUCAGAAACUCAUCAGGACUGCCCUAGGCCUCGCCCUGUGUGUGCUUCCACUUCUGUGUCUUCCUUCUUGCCCUGCCCCACCUUUUAAUCAGGACCACGCCUCCCUCUCCUACCUUGGUGUUGCAAACGUUGUAGCCAUUGCUGUUGGUAGAUUCUUUGACUGAAAUUGAAUGUCCACCUCCUUUAAAAAAAUUUUUAAAAUAUUUACUUAGCUCCUUAAACCAUCCUUAAAAAGAUAUUUUAGGAGUCCUCCAGACUGCUUUGCAUUAACUUCUGAGAUUAUGCUUCUCUGUUUCUGUAGCAACUAAGUGUACCUUUGUGUUACUUAGCACAUAAUUAAUGUAAGCUCCUUGUGAGUGAGAUUCUCUUUUUAUGCUUGUCACCUCUGCCCAGCCCAGGGACUGGUAAACUGUAGAUGUUUAGUGAAAGUAAUUCAAGUAAAGAGAUAAGAAUGCUCAAAGACAUCUCCCACCUGUGUUCCAGAGAAAUUGUUUGCUGAUUGUAUACUUGCACAUUUCUGUAAACAAAUAGGAAAAUCUUUACUCAAAAAGCAUACAUUAGAAAGUUUCUUAUAGAGUAUAAAAGUUAUAUUUACAAGUUUUUAACUGACUUUUCAUAGCUACAUUUAGCGCAUAAAGUAUUUUCAGAUAGAGUAAUUUAGCCACAUGACCUUUAAAUUAUACUGUUUCUCAGUCUUUAAAAACGUGCCCUCUUUCGGCCAGGCACUUUGAUUCACGCCUGUAAUCCCAGCACUCUGGGAGGCCGAGGCGGGUGGAUCACCUGAGGUUAGGAGUUCGAGACCAGCCUGGCCAACAUGGUGAAAACCUGUCUGUACUAAAAAUACAAAAAUUAGCCAGGCGUGGUGGUGCGUGCUCGUAAUCCCAGCUACUUGGGAGGCUGAGGCGGGAGAAUUGCUUAAACCCGGGAGGCAGAGGUUGCAGUGAUCUGAGAUCACACCACUGCACUCCAGCCUGGGCGACAGAGUGAGGCUCUGUCUGAAAAAAAAUGAAAUAAAAUAAAAUAAAUGCCCCCUUUUAGAUAGCCAUAGAAUUUCUUACCUUUAUUUUGCUUUAAAAUAAAAACAUCAUGUUAACCCAAAAUGAAACAAUUGCAAUAUUGAAAAUGUAUCUUUUAAACUUUAGUGGAUGUUUUUCCAUUUUUUAUUUUCUGUUAAGUAUUGCUAAAGGGCCUGGCAUAAAGGAGGGCCACUGAGAUUACGGUAAGAAAAGGGUUCAUUUUCUUCCUGUGGCAGGUGUUCUGACCAGUUGAACACUAGGGAUGCAAAGAUGAAAGGCAACAGGAUUUUUCUGUAAGGCCCGUCAUCCAGCAGGAAUAGGAAAGUGCAUUGUUCUAUGUAAAGCCAUAGAGACUGGCCUCUGGAAGUGGCUGGCUCUCAGCUGCAUGCUUCUUUGGAUAGUCUGCUACAACAGUCACAUAUAUUAUGGUGUAUCCUGCCCUGCACUCUCCUUGUCUCCCCUUCUUGCUGUACUUUUUUCAUAGUAUUUAUGACACUAUAACAUACCAUAUAAUUUACUUACUAAUUUAUGUAUGGCCCGUCUUCUCAUACUUGAAUGUAAACUCUUAUGAGAUCAAGAUUUAUAUUUUGCUCCUCAGUAUGAACCUAAGCCUUAGAACAAUAUCUGGUAGGUAGCAUGCGCUAAAUAGUUGAUGAGUAGAUCCCAGUAUGGUGAACAAGAGGGAUAGAUUGCCAUCUCUUGGAGUUUGGUGUCCAUUGAGACAGGUGGACAAUCACAUAAUCCAAUAAGAAAGUGCAGUGCACUGACAUCCGGCCUGGAUGGGAGGGAUCAGAAGGCUUCCCUGAGGUUGUGAUGGUGGCACCGAGGUUGGAGGGAUGGUGGUGGAGUGAGAGGUCAGCAGAGAGAAUUACCUGUGUAGUGCCCCAAGUGGGAAAGGUGCAGAGUGCUUUGAAGGAACUAGUGUGAACAAGGCUGAAGGAAGAGAACGCGGCUGGGAGGUAGGUGGAGAGUUUUAUUUUACAGAGCUUGGGAGGUCCCAUAUAGGUUGAUUAUUUUGCCCUUUAUCCUAAGACCAGUGGGAAGCAGUUGGAGGAUUUUAUGUCAUAGAAUUGUCUUUUUUAAAUGAUUCUGCUUUGCAGAGUCGUGUGGAAGCAGGGAGUGGUCACAUGUGGGUGUUACUGGGCGGCAAGGUAGGGAAUCUCUUUCUUCUUGUGUACACCUCUCUUCAUAGUUGAAAAGGCCAAGCCCCAGUCUAAAUGAGACCAGCCAGCUUCCUUAAAAUCCCUUUAAUUUGUAUUACAUAUAAUCGUGUAUGUUUAAAAAAUAUUUUAUUUUUUUGAGACAGUUUGUGUCACCCAGGCUGGAGUCCAGUGGCAUGCUCACAGCUCUCUGCAGCCUCGACCUGGGCUUGAGCGAUCUUGCCACCUUAGCCUCCCGAGUAGCUGGGACCCAUGGGUGCAUGCCACCACACCUGGCUAAUUAAAAAAAAAAUUUUUUUUUGUAGAGGUGGCGGGUCUCACUAUGUUGCCCAGUCUGGUCUCGAAUUCCUGGGUUCAAGCAGUCCCAGAGUGUUGGGAUUACAGAUGUGAGCCAUUGCACCUGGCCUAAAAAUGCUUUAAAAUUUGUUUAUAAAAUAUGUCUUAAAUUUGCUAAUAUUUGCCAGUUGUUUAAAGUAUAUUUGUUAUUUCAGAUAAUUUCAAACAUGCCUUUUUUAGGAGUGUCUCUGAAAAAUGAGAACAUUUUGUUUUCACAUUUCAGAGAGCUUUGUUUUUAUUGUCAGUGCUCAAAAUACAGAGAUGAAAACCUAGUGAUCAAUUUGGUAUAGAUGUACAAAUUGCUUCAGUUAUUGUUAUCUGUUAACAUGUUGAACAUUCUCUUUUUAAAAAUAUCAGGUCCUUUAAAAUUUUCUUUAAAGGUGGCUUCAUGCUUUUCUGAGCAUUCUUUUUAUCUUUGUUGAUUACAUAUUUGUAUUUCAUUGUUGAGAUUAUCGUCUGUGUAAUUUUUGCCUUAUCAGUCAGAGAAUACCAGUAACCUUUAGGAGGCAUGUACAGAUUUUUUUUUUUUUUUUUACUGGGUCCAUAAAGGGGGAAAGUUUGGUCAGGUUGGGGAGCAGUCACACUUCUUCCUGAGAGGUAGUAAAUACCAGGCUCUCCAUCUGGAGGAGGGGUCAGUAAAUCACGUUUGCAAAGGAAAAGAUGCGGUAAUUGGUAGGAUUCAGACCUGUGCCGGGAAACCCCAAUGGAUUUCUAGUUCAUUGCUUUAACCAUUCAGUCCUGACUUUAAAAGUAGACUUGAAGUCCCUAUGGGAAGCUACCUUCUAAAAAUCUAGACAUUUGAAAGGAUGAAAGCAUUGUCUCUUGUGCUUUUAGGAGGUUAAAAACAUUUAAACCACGGAUAGAACACUGGCAUUUAGUGUUUCUUGAGUACUGUAAAUACAGUAGCUUACUGUGAAAGUCUUUUUGGGUGGACUUCUGUCUGGCAUGAUUUGUUUUUUUUUUUGAGGUGGAGUCUCACCUGUUUCCCAGGCUGGAGUGCAGUGGCACAGUCUCCGCUCACUGGAAGUUCUGCCUCCCAGGUUCACGCCAUUCUCCUGCCUCAGCCUCCCAAGUAACUGGGACUGCAGGCGUGUGCCACCACGCCCAGCUGAUUUCUUUGUAUUUUUAGUAGAGACGGGGUUUCACCAUGUUAGCCAGGAUGGACUCAAUCUCCUGACCUCAAGCAAUCUGCCUGCCUUGGCCUCCCAAAGUGUUGGGAUUACAGGCGUGAGCCACUGUGCCCGGCCUGCGUAGCAUGAUUUUAAGUUCUAUGUUCCAUAUUCCUCUGUGGUUAAUAUCCAUACCUCCAGUGAUACUUGUUAUUUAUUUAUUUAUUUAUUUAUUUAUUUAUUUAUUUAUUUAACAGACGGGGUCUCGUUCUGUUGCCCAGGCUGCAGGAGUGGAGUGUAGUGGUGUGGCCACUGCUCACUGCAGCCUCCAAUUUCUGAGCUCCAGUGAUCCUCCUGGCUAUUUAAAUAAUAAUUUUUUGAGACAUGAGGUCUUGCCAUGUCACCCAGGCUGGCCUCAGUCUCCUGGCCUCAAGUGAUCCUCCAGCCUCAGCCUCCCAGGUUGCUGGGAAUAUGAGUGUGAGCCCCUGUGCCUUGCUCCAUUGACAGUUGUUACCAGGCUAAAUUGCUAGUUCAGGUUGCCUUUCAGUGGGUCACUUGGAGCAGGGGUCCCUAACUCCCAGGUUGUCCGACCCGUACCCAUCAUGGCCUGGUAGGAACUGCGCUGCACAGCAGGAGGUGAGCAGCAGGGUGAGUGAGCAUUACUGCCUGAGCUCCACCUCCUCUCAGAUGAGCAGUUGCGCUAGAUUCUCAUAAGAGCUCAAAUCCUACUGUGCACUGCACAUGCAAGGGAUCUAGGUCGCAUGCUCCUUAUGAGAAUCUAGUGCCUGAUGAUCUGAGGUGGAACAGUUUCAUCCUGAAAGCAUCCUCCUCACCACCCCCCACCCCCUGACCCCUCCGCUCUGUCUGUGGAAAAAUUGUCUUGCAUGAAACCUGUCAGUCCCUGGUGCCAAAAAAGAUUGGUUACCGCUGACUUGGAGUACUGACCAUUGUGAAAAUGAGUAACUGAUGAAUCAGCAAUAGUUGCUUCUUCACGCUGUCAGUGAAGACCAAAGAAUGAAUAUGGGAAGCAGUAUUACCAGUGUUGCUGCGUGUGCACGUGGCCUUCAGUUUUUCCCUGCUCUUCCCAUUUCUUUGUACACACCGAUGAAUUUAAUCUCUUCUGCUGAAAUCAUUAUUCUUUAGGGCUCAGUACAGGAGAGUUAAACCUAAGCAUGAAAGGACUGGAAAUGGGAUGUAGAAUUGCCAAAUAAACUGUAGAAGCAUUGAGGCACUUAAAAAUCUCCAUGACCUGGAGAAAUUCCAGUGAAGAGUAAACUUUUGCAGUGUGCCUUAGGAUUCCGAGUGACCACAAGUUUUAUUAUCUUUCAGGCAAGGCCACACAGAUUCUUGGCAUACUAUUUCCUGUAAGUUCAGAAUUUUGGAAGUGUGUUGGUCAUUGUGGUAGUCCUCCCCCUCCCCGCGUCCCCCUGCCAACCUUACAGGAAAGAAAGAAGUGGUAGUUUUAUUCUGUUAUUGAGAAUAGGUUUUUCAUGAAAUCACAUGAAGUUACAGCUCAACAUAAAUAACUGUAGACUAGAUGUUUUCCCAAAAUCGUUAUAUGGCCACAAAUUGUGUUAGAUAAUUAUAUGAGCAAGGCAAAUAAAUGCUGGAUCAUUAACUUCCAGUUUUCUUUCUUUCUUUUUCUUUUUUUUUUUGAGAUGGAGUUUCACUCUUGUUGCCCAGGCUGGAGUGCAAUGGUGCGAUCUCGGCUCACUGCAACCUCCACCUCCUGGGUUCAAGCGAUUCUCCUGCCCCAGCCUCCUGAGUAGCUGGGAUUACAGGCAUGCACCACCACGCCUGGCUAGUUUUGUAUUUUUAGUAGAGACAGGGUUUCUCCAUGUUGGUCAGGCUGCUCUCGAACUCCCCACCUCAGGUGAUCCGCCUGCCUUGGCCUCCCAAAGUGCUGGGAUUACAGGUGUGAGCCACCAUGCCUGACCCUUAACUUCCAGUUUUCAAUUUGAUGUUGGGAAGUGUGGUUAGGUAAAUUUAUUGUAAAGCAUAUAUUUACGAAAUGUUUAAUAAUAAUAAUAGUGAACAUAACAUUUAAUCAGCCUUAACCCAGUUGCAUGGAGUGUUUUCUUUUUAUCAGUUCCAUCGUUAUCAGUCUGGAAUUAAAAGACUGAAGGAACCUUUAAUUCUUUUUAAUUCCUUUUUUUUGAGACAGAGUCUCACUUUGUCCCCCAGGCUGAAGUGCAGUGGCUGUAUCUUGGCUCACUGCAAUCAUCACCUCCUGGGUUCAAGUGAUUCUCGUGCUUCAACCUCCAGAGUAGCCAGGACUACAGGCACGUCACCAUGCCCAGCUUAUUUUUAUAGUUUUAGUAGAGACAGGGUUUCUCCAUAUUGGCCAGGCUGGUCUGCAACUCCUGGCCUCAAGUGAUCUGCCUGCCUUGGCCUCCCAAAGUGCUGGGAUUACAGGCCUGAGCCACUGUGUCUGGCCUGAUUAAUUCUUAAUUCAUAAAAUGUUAGGUGUGAAUUAAAUAGUACUUUUGAAGUAAGAUGUUUAUAUUCUAAGACUGUGAGUUUUGUUCUACGUUAUUUUGUCAACUGAGAUUUGGUAACUAGUUUGUGAAAAUAAUUGUCAGAAAAACAGUGUAAUAUUGCAGUUGCAGUCUUAGGAUUUUAGAUCUCUGAAGACUCAGAAACUGAAGCCCAUGAGGUAAAAUUAAUUAGAGAUACAGCUGGCUAGUUGGUGACAGAGCUAGGACUGUAACGAGCCUCCUCUUUAAGUCCAGCAUCCCGUUGCACUGUAAUUGCAGAGUUUACUGUGGUCGCUGUUAAGGCGCACCCUCCGCUGUGGUAUAUCAAAAGAAAUUGGUGAAAGCAUUAAUUUUAUGUAUGUUAGAUAAUUUAAAUAAGUGUUUUAACUUUUUGAGGUAGAUUUUUAAAGCAGUUAUUAGACUGUGCUUUUUAAAAGAUUGAAAUAUAUUUACUCCAGGAAAAUUAAGUGUUUUGUCAUUUUAGAUAAUCCAUUAACCUUAAUCCAAAUAGGGAGGUGCUAAUUGGUGUUCUGGUUAACACCCUCCGGUUUGUAUCGUGUAAUCAGACUGCAGCUUACAGUUCAUCUUUGAGAAAUAGUCUAAGAGAAAUUCAUGUAAAUUAAAUGGUUUUCUUCCUAAAGCAUUCAGGGAGAGUUGUUCAUUUUAACGUCCACGCUGUUAACACAGGAGUCUGUGUGCAGUCUUGGAUCCAACUUCAACACCUGUGUUCAUACCCGUCACCUUUGUGUAGAGGAACUCACACUAGAGAUAAUGUGACUUGCUGUGAGCUCUCCUGGCCUUUGGUUUACUGUCCUCAGGCAACUGUGGUGUGUGUCAGGAUCUUUCACACUAUCUUACACUCUUAAGAAACUACAGCAAAUUGCAACAACUCCCACCCUCAACAAUGUAUUGGACUUGUAAUUCAGAGGAUUGAAAGCCCCCUCCCUUUUUUCCCCCCAUUUAUUCUUCAGAACACUUGUUUUACUGUUUGGGAAACUGAGUCUUGGUGACAGUUUGCUUUACAUCAUCCAAUACAGGAAGAACAGAAAAUGGGAACUUUAUAGCUUCUUGCUUAUAAGCCUUUUGCGUGGCAGGAGAGAAUUCUACCACUGAACGACCCAUGCACCGAUGCUUAUAAGCCUUUUGCAAGUAAUACCCAGCUCUUAGAGAGGGUCAGCGUUCUGUGCAGCACCUUGGAUCCAAAUAACAUGAUGUAUUUGGGGGCUUAAGUCACACAUCAUAGUUCAGCAUCAGAGAUACAGGCCCUGUACUUAAUAGUUUAAUAACUUAAUUAUUUAAAUAUUUAAUAGUUGAAUAAUUACUGUUAAACAAAGUAUUAAUAGUAAUUUUCAUUGUGGUUAUCUUUUUUUUGAGACGGAGUCUCACUCAGUUGCCCAGGCUGGAGUGCAGUGGCUUGAUCUCCGCUCACUGCAAACUCCGCCUCUCGGGUUCACGCCAUUCUCCUGCCUCAGCCUCCCUAGUAGCUGGGACUACAGGCGCCCGCCACCACGCCCAGCUAAUUUUUUUGUAUUUUUUUUUAUUAGAGAUGGGGUUUCACCGUGUUAGCCAGGAUGGUUGCGAUCUCCUGACCUCGUGAUCCACCCACCUCGGCCUCCCAAAGUGCUGGGAUUACAGGCGUGAGCCACCGCACCUGGCCCAUUGUGGUUAUCUUUGAAGCCAGAGAUAUCCUAUGCUACAAGAUUGAGUAAAGUUAUCUACAUUUCCGAACAGUAAUUCAGAAUCAUUGGAAGUGAUAGGAAUUUUCAAUGGCUGAUUCUUAUAGUUUGCCUGAAACUUUUUUUUUUUUUUUUUUUUUUUUGAGACAGGGUCUCACUCUGUUGCCAGGCUGGAGUGCAGUGGCGUGAUCUUGGCUUAUUGUGGUCUUGACCUCCCAGUCUCAAGCGGUCCUCCCUCCUCAGCCUCCCGAGUAGCUGGGACUACAGGCACGUGCCACCACACCUGGUUAAUUUUUGUAUUUUUUUGUAGAGAUGGGUUUUCAUCUUGUUGCACAGGCUGGUCUCAAACUCCUGGGCUCAAGCAAUCCUCCUGCCUUGGCCUUCAAAAGCACUGGGAUUACAGGCAUGUGCCAUCAUCCCCGGCCUGUCUGAAACUCUUUUUGUGAUGUUAGUGUUGACCUAAAAUGAAGAAGCUGAGUGAAGAGUUUAUUUGGGCCAAGCAUGAUGAUUGCAACCCAGGAGCAUAGACCAAGUUGCUCAGCGGCAGUUACAAGUGGAUUUUUAUGAUGGGAUGAUGUAUGACGGUGCUGGGAAGGCUCAUUCUCAGCCCUCAGUCAAGUCACUGAUUUAUGUAACUGUCAUUGCUUGUUAAAUCUUCUGUAGUCUUUGAAUUUCAUGCUUUUGGUUUUCUUAGAGGUAAAACAAUAAAAUACAUAGUAAAAAUCCUAUUACAUUGGAGAUUCAAUCCAAAUUGUAGGAAAACAAUAAAAACUCAAACACAAUGGUUAAGGCUGGAAUCUAAUAACAUGGGUACUAUAGUUUUCUUAUGAAGCAUAAUUUUUUCUCUCUCCAGUCCCCAUUUUUACUGAAGAUAUAAAUCUUAGGAGGACCAGCUUACUUGCAAAAUAAGUUUUAGUAUUAUACUUGGGCUGAUUAUUUGCAUAAAAUGCAACAAGAAUAAUGAUUGGCCAUAUAGGUUCUUUAAGUUGUCUUUGCUGGAACUUUCAUAAGGAAUUUUGGAUUCAACUAUAAAGCCUCAAGGCUAGGAAGCCAAGCCAAGGACUAUGCUGGUAAUACUUACAUGAAUUGGGUGAAUUCCUCUCUUCUUGAGGUCGCAAAAUAUCUUGAGGUUCCUGGGCUUGUCAGAAAGUAAGAUUGUUUUACUUGCUGCACAUCAGGAACCUUGUAAAGGAGCCAUGUAAACAAGGUACCAGGCUAGUCUUUCCAACAGGCUUUUUAUUGGCUCUACAUAGUCAACCUCUGUUCUUUAAACCAGUCUGGUCAUAUCUUAAAAUACGCCAUUCCAGUCAAGAGUGUCGGUAGAAUAACCAGUGUCUUAAUUGUGUCCUGUUACAAUAAACCGGUUUUUAUUGAACUUAAAACGCAUAUAAUUAGACUGUCAUAAAAUAAGAGUACUCAUGAAUAGUUUAUACAUUUUGGAGAAAUAAGGUAGAGAGUAAGGUGAAUGUUUCAGUCUUGCUCAUAAAGUUAUGUUUUACCCAUUUGCUACAAGCUAUAAAAAGCUUGAAAGAAAAAAGCUUCCUCGACUUGGGAAAACAAAACAUGAAAAGAAUCAGCAAUGUUUCAAACAAAAAGUCGUCAAAAUCAUUUCAGUCAUCUGUAAUUUCAGUCCCAUGUAAUUAAGUUUUAUUCUGCUUGAUAUACAGAGUUAGCAAUCAUCAUGAACACAACAGUUUAUUAGAGUUCUGAAAGUUUUUACUUACUCCAAUGAUAAUGGUCUUCAAAAUUAUCAGAAACUUGUAUUCAAGAGUACUUACCACCUGGCGCAGUGGCUCAUAGCUAUAAUCUCAGCACUUUAGGAGGCCAAGAAGGGAGGAUCGCUUGAGGCCAUGAGUUCAAGACCAGCCUGGCCAACAUAGCAAGACCCCCAUCUCGACAAAAAAUAGAAAAAUUAGCCAGGUGUGGUGGUGUGUGCUUAUAGUUGUAGCUACUUGGGAGGCUGAGGUGGGAGGAUCACUUAGGUCCAGGAGUUUGAGGUUGUAGUGAGUUAGAAAGUGCCACUGCACUCUAAUCUGCACAACAGAGCAAGACCUUGUCUCUUUAUUUAUUUGUUUGUUUUGAGACGGAGUUUCACUCUUGUUGCCCAGGCUGGAGUGCAAUGGCGUGAUCUCGGCUCACUGCAACCUCCACCUCACAGAUUCAAGUGAUUCUCCUGCCACGGCCUCCCAAGUAUCUGGGAUUACAGGCAUGCGCCACCACGCCUGGCUAGUUUUGUAUUUUUAGUAGAGAUGGGGUUUCUCCGUGUUGGUCAGGCUGGUCUCGAACUCCUGACCUCAGGUGAUCUGCCUGCCUUGGCCUCCCAAAGUGAUGGGAUUACAGGCAUGAGCCAUCGCGCCCAGCCAAGACCUUGUCUCUUAAAAAAAAAAUUAUUUUCCAUGAAUUCCCUUGAAGAAAAAGCAAAUUUUUGACUGUAGCCAAGUGUAAACUACUUUUUGAGAAGAGUCAAAGUAGAACAAUAAUUGUCUGUGGAUGCCAAAAGACUUAGAGUAGCUACAGUUAAAGACACAAUUUACAAGGAAAUUUGGUUAUUUUUGUGGCAUACAACAAUUUAACAUAAUAACCAUAAUUAUGUCUGACAUAUCAAGACAUAUCAGGAUUUCAGAAAUCUCAUGUAACGUUGGAACACACAUUAAUACCAUGCACACAAAUAUAACCCAAAGUUAAACACCAUUUCUUAUUUGACAAAGCUUCACAUACAAUUUUAACAUACCAAUUAAGCCUAAUAGGUCUCUCUCGGACUUCCAGGGGGUUCCUUUUGGAAAAGACUUAAUUUUAGAAUUUGAAAGUUGAUUUUGGGAAAUGUGUCAAAUAUUGAAAAGGAUGUUGUUCAAAACAGAAUCACAGGUUGCUGUAAAAUAAUAGUCAUUUAGCCAGAUAAUUGAAAUAUUUCAAAAAGCAAAAACCUUUUUUUUUUUUUUUUUUGAGGCGGAGUCUCGCUCUGUCUCCCAGGCUGGAAUGCAGUGGCGCCAUCUGGGCUCACUGCAACCUCCGCCUCCUGGGUUCACGCCAUUCUCCUGCCUCAGCCUCCUGAGUCGCUAUUCUCUUGCCUCAGCCUCCUGAGUAGCUGGGACUACAGGCGCCCACCACCACAUCCAGCUAAUUGUUUGUAUUUUUAGUAGAGAUGGGGUUUCACCGUGUUAGCCAGGAUGGUCUCGAUCUCCUGACCUCGUGAUCCACCCACCUUGGCCUCCCAAAGUGUUGGGAUUACAGGUGUGAGCCACUGCACCCGGCCAAAAAAACAAAAACUUUUUCUCUUUUUUGAUACUCAGUUUUCUAAACAAUCAAAAGACCUAAAAAGACGACAUGAGACCAACAGAAUCUUUUUUUUUCCAGCUUAUUCAAAAGGUGAGCAAAAGUCUUUUGUUAUCCUCAUUAAUAUUAUAUGAACAUCUUGUUCAAAAGAGAAAAAUAAAUUUUACCUUUGCAUCAGUAUAUUGUCAGUGCUAGAGCCUUUUAUUUUUUUUUCCCCUGGAGACAGGGUCUGCUCUGUUGCCUGGGGUGGAGUGUAGUGGUGUAAUCAUAGCUCGCUGCAGCCUCAAACUCCUGGGCUCAAGUGAUCCUCCCACCUCAGCCUCCUGAGUAUAAAGCUAUUUUAAUGAAACUGUCCAUCAAAUCUCAAUCAGCUUGGACCAUGCAAGAUAAAAUUUCCAUAAACUUUUUACAACCACUUAAAAUUUUUUCUUAAAGAGCAGACCAGUGCUCCAAGAAAAGUCUGCUGUUCUGACACAGGGGCCCAGACUCUGGCCCUGCAUUUGUGUACGUUGUAUAUUAAUGUUCAAUUUUAGCAAAACUAAAUAAUUCUCUUCUAAUUUAGCAAGCUUGAUUACACACAAUUUUUUUUUCACAAGAUUAAUCUUCCACAAAUGGUCUACAACUUGCUGAAGCCUUUGGUUUUGACCUAUACCUCUUUUUUUUUUUUUUCUUUGCUGGGGGGUGGGCGGUGGGGGCGGGUGGGGCGCUGAGUCUACCUCUGUAGCACAGGCUGGAGUGCAGUGGCAUGAUCUCGGCUCACUGCAACGUCCGCCUCCCGGGUCUCGGUUCAAGCAAUUCUCUUGCCUCAGCCUCUCGAGUGGCUGGGAUUACAGGCAUGCGCCACCAUGCCCAGCUAAUUUUUGUGUUUUUAGUAGAGAUGGGGUUUCACCAUGUUGGUCAGGUUGGUCUUGAACUCCUGACCUCAUGAUCCACCCACCUUGGCCUCCCAAAGUGCUGGGAUUACGGGUGCGAGCCACCACGCCUCACUCGACUUUUUUUUUUUUUUGGCUGAGUCUUCCUCUGUAGCCCAGGCUGGAGUGCAGUGGCGUGAUCUCGGCUCACUGCAACCUACCUUUCUUUUUUAUAUUGGCAUUUUACCUUAAGAGAAAAACUUACUUUCCUUUCCCCCUUAUCAUUUUGACCAUACAAAGAUCUCUGUGUACAAGGGAAAAACAAUUAGUCUCUUUUCAACUUUCCUUACAUCUUUUAAAAUAUGCUCUGUAUAUAAAAUUGUUUCUUAUACCUAAUAGUUUUAAUUACGUAUAUUAACUACAAUUUUAACUCUUAGUAACUCGAAUUUCCAGUGAAAAACCCAGGAAGUAAUUUUGAACUGUUUUAUACCACAUGACAACAAUUUCUGAAUAUUUCCUCAAUUUUUGUUUAUAACCUAAAUAUAUUUUGUUUAUAACCUAAAUAUAUUUAACUUUUCUGUACCCUAUAAAUGAGAUAGAUAUUUUAUGAUUACCUGUUAAUUAACAUAACAUGGCUUUAAGAUUAAAUUUUUGAAAAGGGUUUGUGAAACUAUGAAAAGUUUGUUUAUAAAUAUCUUAUUUACAUUCAUCUAAUUUAUUCUUCGUUAUUUUUAUUUUUUUUUGAGACCCAGCCUUACUGUGUCACCCAGGCUGGAGUGCAGUGGCUUGAUCUCAACUCACUGCAACGUCAGCCUCCUGGGUUUAAGUGAUACUCCCACCUCAGCGUCCCAAGUAGCUGGGACUACAGGCGUGCGCUGCCAUGCUCAGCUAAUUUUUGUAUUUUUGGUAGAGAGGGGGUUUCACUGUAUUGGCCUGGCUGGUCUCGAACUCCUAGUGAUGGGAUUACAGGCGUGAGCCACUGCACCCGGCCCUAAUUUAUUCAUUCUUAACAGUUAUUAUGCUUGAAUAGUUCAUUAAACAAAGUUAGCCAUCAUCUCAAUUUAUUUCUUUGUUAAUCAUUUCUACAGCCUGUGAAACCCUAGAGUUAAAUGAAUGAGUAUUUGCUGAUGAGAAGACAUAGCUCCUUUCAUUAAACCAACAAACUAAUCUUUAUUUACCAAAGAUCUACCCAAGUCAUGAACUAAAAGACAUUUGAGUUUCUAUUUGUCUGAUGAAAUAUUUGAUUUAAGCACUUGUGUUUUCUUUAAGCUGGUUAAUUAGAGGUGUUUCAUAUAUUUUGGUAGUGAAAUAUCACAUAUAUAUGAUACAUAAAAGUAAAGACAUGCAGAUGCACUAACAGAAGCAGAUCUUACAGUUUUAUAAGAUUUUUCAUUUGCUAGUGAAAAUAAUUCCCCCCCUCCUUUAGACUAUCAGUCUCUUAAUUAUCUGUUCCACUCCCCUAAACAAUUCAGAUUGCUAGACAACCCUAAAUUUUCACUUCCAAAGACAUGACUCUCAGGUGAAAACUUACAUCCCAAAGGCAGAGAACUUAGAUCUAAACACUAUUAUUUGUUGAAUCAAAAAGGGAUAGUCAGGAAUUGCCAGGAAAAGCAUCAAGCAAAGGGAAGGUUUGCUCUGUAAACUUUAAGCCAAUGUUUUUUUCAUUGUAAAAGUUUAUAGUGGCUUGAGUGCAGGAAGGGAGAUGCCCUUACAGAUGUCAGUUUCUUUUAUAAAGAGGUUCAGGAUAGCUAGCUAAAUGUCAGAAAGUCAUAUUUUGUGUUUUUGUUUUUGAUGGGGUCUCACUGCCAUUCAGGUUGGAGUGCAGUGACCUCUGCAACCUCUGCCUCCCAGGCUCAAGUGAUGCCUCCCGAGUAGCUGGGACCACAGGCGCACGCCACCAUGCCCCGCUAAUUUUUUUUUUUGAAUUUUUUUUUUUUUUUUUUGUCAAGACGAGGUUUCUCCAUGUUGCCCAGGCUGGUUUUGACCUCUUGAGCUCAAGGGAUCUGCCCGCCUCAGCCUCCCAAAGUGCUGAGAUUACAGGUGUGAGCCAAUGCGCUCGGCCAUAGAACGUCAUAUAUUGGAGAGCAGUCUGGUUAGAUAGGUGGUCUUCCAACCUAGAUGUUUCUUGGUUAGAUUACUGACUUUAAUGAGUGGAAAAAGAAAACAUUUGCAGUUUCUAGGGCCUAAUACUUAAAUUUGAAAAGCAGGCACAGAUGAAAGGCAGAGCAUCUAGAUCAAGCCUGUCCUACCCUCGGCCUGGGAUGGCUUUGAAUGCGGCCCAACACAAAUUUGUAAAUGUUCUUAAAACAGUAUGAAGAUUUUUUUUUUUUGCGAUUUUUUUUUCUUUUCUUUUCUCUCUCUCUUUUUUAAGCAUCUCAUCAGCUGUCAUUAGUGUUAGUGUAUUUUAUGUGUGGCCCAAGAUCAGUGUGGCCCAGGGAAGCCAAAGAUUGGACACCCUUGAUCUACAUCUUUAAAAAUCAAGGAUUCCACUUUUAUUAAUAGACUGAAUCUUGGGUCCCCCAAAGGAGGGAAACGCCAUAACACCUGCCACGCAGAGCUUCCACAGUGCUUCUCACUGCAAGGACAUUCCCUCAAGGUUGGUGAGUGGCCCAGUCAGCCCACUGUGACCAGCCCAUCCCAUAUGGGAAUCUUAUCACUUGGUGGUGAGCACUCUCCUAACCUCCAAGUGUUCAAACUGCAUCUGUCUAAAUGUGUAAAGAAACAGUAGCCAUCCUGCAGUAACAACUAUUCAGUCAGCCACUUCCCAAACUGCAGCUUUCACCAGUGACUUGUCCGCCAUUGCACACACAAAAGUCAGGGUCUCUCUCACAGUGUAAAGUAAUCCCGAAAGCCCCCGAAAACCACGAAAUUGGACAGCGCAAUGCAAAAGGGAGCAGAGCUUUAGACCUGAGAGGAAACUACUCACAACUCUUCAGACUCCGUACUGAAAACAGAAGACCCUUCCAGAAGGGGCAUCCUGAGGUUAGCAUUACACUUCUCCCAGUGGAGCCCAUGACUUCUGAUCAGGACGCUAAGGUUGUGGCUGAACCGCAGACGCAGAGAGUCCAGGAGGGCAAGGACAGCGCUCAUCUGAUGAAUGGUCCUAUAUCUCAAACCACUUCUCAGACAAGUUCCAUCCCACCUUUGAGUCAGGUACCAGCAACUAAGGUUUCAGAGCUGAACCCUAAUGCAGAAGUGUGGGGGGCUCCUGUGUUACAUCUGGAAGCAAGCAGUGCUGCUGACGGUGUGAGUGCUGCAUGGGAGGAGGUGGCUGGCCACCACGCAGACCGUGGCCCGCAGGGAUCGGAUGCCAAUGGUGAUGGUGACCAGGGCCAUGAGAAUGCCGCAUUGCCAGACCCGCAGGAGUCGGACCCAGCAGACAUGAACGCUCUCGCUCUGGGUCCCUCAGAAUAUGACUCUCUGCCUGAAAAUAGCGAGACAGGAGGAAAUGAGUCUCAACCAGACAGCCAGGAAGACCCCCGAGAAGUACUUAAAAAAACAUUGGAAUUCUGCUUAUCUAGGGAGAACCUUGCUAGUGACAUGUAUCUUAUAUCACAGAUGGAUAGUGACCAGUAUGUGCCAAUCACAACGGUGGCUAACCUCGACCACAUCAAGAAGCUCAGCACUGAUGUGGACUUGAUUGUGGAAGUGCUAAGAUCUUUACCUUUAGUCCAAGUGGAUGAAAAGGGAGAAAAAGUAAGGCCAAAUCAAAAUCGCUGCAUAGUAAUAUUGCGUGAAAUAUCUGAAUCUACCCCCGUGGAAGAAGUAGAAGCACUAUUUAAAGGAGAUAAUUUACCAAAAUUUAUAAACUGUGAAUUUGCAUAUAAUGAUAAUUGGUUUAUUACAUUUGAAACAGAAGCUGAUGCACAACAGGCUUACAAAUACCUUCGAGAAGAAGUCAAAACUUUUCAAGGAAAACCAAUUAAGGCACGGAUAAAAGCAAAGGCAAUAGCUAUAAACACAUUUUUGCCAAAGAAUGGAUUUAGACCCCUGGACGUGAGCCUGUAUGCCCAGCAGCGCUACGCGACGUCGUUCUACUUCCCUCCCAUGUACAGCCCCCAGCAGCAGUUCCCCCUGUACAGCCUGAUCACUCCCCAGACGUGGUCAGCAACGCACAGCUAUCUUGACCCACCCUUGGUAACUCCAUUUCCAAAUACUGGAUUUAUAAAUGGGUUUACGUCUCCAGCGUUCAAGCCUGCGGCGUCUCCUCUGACUUCUCUCAGACAGUAUCCUCCUCGAAGCAGGAAUCCUAGUAAAUCUCAUCUGCGGCAUGCGAUUCCUAGUGCAGAGAGGGGACCUGGGUUAUUAGAAAGUCCUUCAAUAUUUAACUUCACUGCAGAUCGAUUAAUUAAUGGUGUCCGGAGUCCACAAACAAGGCAAGCAGGUCAAACUAGAACACGGAUUCAAAACCCUUCAGCAUAUGCCAAGAGAGAGGCUGGGCCUGGGCGUGUGGAGCCAGGCAGUCUCGAAUCCUCUCCUGGUUUAGGGAGGGGAAGGAAGAAUUCCUUUGGCUACCGGAAGAAAAGGGAGGAGAAGUUUACAAGCAGCCAGACACAGUCUCCAACGCCACCAAAGCCUCCGUCGCCAAGCUUCGAGCUGGGGCUGUCCAGCUUCCCUCCAUUACCUGGAGCUGCCGGCAAUUUGAAGACAGAGGACUUGUUUGAAAACAGGCUAUCUAGCUUGAUAAUAGGACCAUCCAAAGAAAGGACCCUCAGUGCAGACGCAAGCGUGAACACCCUUCCUGUAGUGGUCUCCAGAGAGCCCUCGGUGCCGGCUUCUUGUGCUGUAUCAGCAACGUACGAGCGAUCCCCCUCCCCAGCUCAUUUACCCGAUGAUCCCAAGGUGGCGGAGAAACAGAGGGAAACCCACAGUGUGGACAGACUUCCUUCCGCCCUCACUGCGACCGCGUGUAAAUCGGUGCAGGUGAACGGAGCCGCCACGGUACGUACCUCGUGCCUGCCUUCCUGCACGACAGCCGCGAGGCUCUGGUGUGAACAGACGCUGCGCACUCCUGCACCUGCUCGUUUUUUAAUCACAUCUAAUUUGGAAUUGCGAAAGCCCAGCUACGCAGAGAUUUGUCAGAGAACGAGUAAAGAGCCUCCUUCUUCCCCAUUGCAACCCCAAAAAGAACAAAAGCCAAACACUGUUGGUUGUGGGAAGGAGGAAAAGAAGCUGGCAGAGCCCGCAGAGAGAUACCGGGAGCCCCCAGCCCUCAAGUCCACACCUGGAGCCCCCAGAGACCAGAGGCGGCCGGCGGGGGGCCGGCCCUCGCCCUCGGCCAUGGGGAAGCGUCUCAGCCGAGAGCAGAGCACUCCCCCCAAGUCUCCUCAGUGAAAACCGUACGUCUGGGAGGGGUCGCAGAGCGCUGUGUUAACCACAAACGAGACACUCUCCCACUCAGUGCGAGGGCGAGCCGCUGGUUAGGAGCUUGCAGUGUCUGAGGCCUGUGGGAUCCUCAAGUUGGUUUUCUUCUGUGAGUUGGAUUCUCCCCCUCUUGAAAAAAAAUCGAUUUUUCAGGAUUUAAUUAAUACAAACCUUAUUUUAGGUUGGUGCUUAACUGGAGGUGAUGCAUAAGUCUGAUUUUUUUUUCCAAGAUAGAAAAAGCAUUUAUCCUAACAAAUUGGUAUUUUUUAUUAAGCCUCCAUGUGGCUCUGAAUGCAAGCUAUAUAUAGUGAGUUUUUCUAAAUUAAGGGAACUCUGCUUUUUUUUUUUUUUUUUAAGUAACUGGUCUGUAAGUGCAUAUCUCUAGAACGUCCCCGCAGAUGAAUGAGGGCCAGUGGCCUUGGCAGAGGCAGGUGUGGCCUCGUAGAGGCAGUGCUGGCCGCGCCAGGGCAUCAGUGCUGAUGUGGGAGCUGUGCUUCCACCUAAGCCGUUGGUAGGGGACUGUGGCAUUUAAGAAUGUAGAGAGCGCAUCCUUUUUGAUCUCCUGGGCGGAGUGAACCUGCAGGGGCCACCCCAGAAACCUUGGUUCUGAUGCACUGCAAGCAAGUAACCAGCUUCUCACUCCAGUUUCAAGUGGCUAUUAUGUAAUAUAAAUUCAAAGCACAUUGUGAAUAGAACCUACAUGAAAACAUACACUUUGUUGCCCACUGACAUGUUACCAGAAGUUGUACCAUGAUGUUGUUUUGACCCCUGUGAGCUGAUGGCCCCGGCCCUGCUCUGUGCACAUUUCUGUCCGUGUUCCCCAGCACUCUGGUUGGAGAGAGUCCACAUCUUCAGCUCCGUGUGGACAUCUCCCUGUACCUCUGCAUCAGCACAUGGAUUUAAGAGUUAUGUAAUCGUGAGAGAAUGGUGUUUGUGGUUUUUCCCCCUCUUUGGCUGGUGGAGGAUAAAGUUCCUGCUCUUUUACCUCCAAGACGAGGGCCUCAUUGAUUCACUUCCAGAAGUGCUGCACUUCUGAAGAACAAGGAUGCACUAAAGUUAGCAAGUUUAUAAUAAAGUUAAAUAUAAAUUAUUUUGUUUUAAAAUGCCUCAAAUUUUUCUUUAUUCUAAGCAGCAAACAUUAAAAUAAGAAUAUUUCCUGCUAAAUGUAACCAUACACUUUAUUCCACAAAAUGUUAUUUAACAAGACUGAGGGUUUUUUUUAAGAAAAAAUUAUUUCCAUCCAAUAUUUAAAGACUUGAAUUUUAUUUAAACUUGAAAAUGACUUUGCCUUAACUUUUGUAUAAGACAGCUUAGAGUCCAUGGAGCCCGGCCCUGGGUUGGCGUGAGUGGGUCAGAGUUACUCAGUUACUGCGUGGAUCUCCUGUCGCUAGUUUUACUGAGUAAGCAUACUGUAGUACAAGAGCUAGUAGUAGUUUUUGUAAUAUACCUUAAAGAUCUUCAACAGUUGAUCUUUUUUCAGAAUGUUGGAAAAUCCUGUAAAUGCAAAUAGUCAAUACUGUAUUAAAUACGUGCACUUGGAGUGUGCUUCGCUUGUACAGUUGUAAAUAAUCAGAACAUAUGAAAAAGGUACCCUACAGAGAAAAUUCUGAUACAGAUUAUUGAUAUAUUAUAAAUGUUGCUGUUGAGCGGGAUGUAGAUAAACUAAAUGUUGUGGUUUGAAUAUUAUUUUGAUUUGUUGAGAUUUUCUUUUUUCUCUUACAUCGGUGUGUUGAACUGAUUCUGCCUCUUUGCUGCAAAAGGGAAUUGGAAAGUCUUAUUAAAAGCCUCCAGAUGUUUUCAUACUCUUUUAAAAUGUAUGUAAAUGCAUACUAAUCAUAUCUAAUGUGAAAGAGUUUUAAAGUAUAUAGAGAGCAAAAACUGGCAGGAUCGUAAGUGAAGGUGACUAGUAAUCUAAUUUAAAUCACCUGCAGCUAAGCAUGAUUGACCCUGCCAGAGGAAAACAUGCCUAUUUGACCAUUUCCUUUAAAGCAGUUGCCAUUAUUCAAAUACAGAGAAAUAGCCACAGGGCUAGUGUUUUUCAAAUGCAUUUUAAAGAACAUGGGGAUUUUUUUUUGUAGUUGUCAGUUCACUGACCAAAAAAAAAAAAAAAAUCAGAAAUAAUUGAUCUGUGAAACCCAAACUCUCAAUACUCAGAAAGCUGGGAGGCAACCUCGAGGCCUGGGCCUACGAGCUGCAUCUUCGCUACGGAAGGGCCAGGGCGCCAUCAGCCAUUCCCAAAACACAAGGCCUGCCCGUCCGCCAGUGAGUCCUUGGUUUUUAAUAAUGAGAAGUCCUUUCCCCCAAGGUGUGAGCAUUGCAGCGCAGUGUGUGUGUGUGGUUAGAGCCAGCUUAGUCCUUCACUUUGUCGACCGAAGUGGGAGCUCAACAGCUGCAUGAGGAGGGCAGCGCGUGCAUUAGCCAGUCGCCACUGGAGGGCUCUGCUGCCCUCCGGUCAAUACACUGUAGUUACUGCCUAGCCAGCAGCAGUCUUCUGCAUCAAGAACUGAAACGUUGCUCGGAGGUGAUUUUUAUAGCAUCCUUUUUAAUUAAAGGUGAAAUACAGAUUGCUAUAUAAUGUCUGAAAAAACCUGAUACUACUUCAAGAGUUUCUGCUCAGAAGAAAAUGAGAGUUAUCAUAAUAGGAAGCUGUGGCGGUCCAUGCCAACUGUGCUGUGUCACAUACAGCGAUGAGAGUGGCUUUCAUACUUUUUUUUUUUUUAAGUUAACACCCUCCUUUACCCCCAGCAGUAUCUCAGGUUAUAGAAUCAGAGAUGCAGCAGUGACAAAUGGCAUUUUAACUUGUAAAAUCGUGUGAUGAUGCUUAUCAUUUUGAAAUAGAAGAAUAAAAACCUGGUCCCGUUUCACCAGACAUGAAUUUCAAGUGGAGUCGUCGUUCUCUGAGAGUGAGUGUCUUGACAUUUUCACCCAGGCCCUCCUGUCAUCACAUCACCGGCUGUCACUGGCGGGUGGCCGUAAACGUCCUGCGUUGCUAUAUUAGGAUCUCUGCAGUUCAGGCUUCAAAACCAGUUCAGUGUAUCCGGGCGACGGGUAGUGGUGGUGCAUGCCUGUCUGUGUGCCCCGCUGGCGAGCUGUAGUUGCGGCUUGCGUGCCUCGCGGCCCACUACAGGGCUGCAGACAAUCGAGGCGAGGGCGCUGGCCGCCAGCAGCUCACAGCGCGGGGGUCAUGUGGUCGCUCCUCGAGGGUUUCGUUUUUGUUCUGCUUCAUUAAGACUGGAAUCAAGCUUACAUGUAAACUAUUGGUAAUUUAAGUUUCCUUUUGUGUCAUUCAGUGUAAAACUGUCUAAUUUGAAAAAAAAUGUAGGUUAUGAAAAUAAAGAUUUAGGCACUGUUCAAUUUUUCUUUUGAUUUUUUUUAAAUUAAAAUUUCUUCAAUAAUGCAUCUUUUCUAAACAUAGUUUUUUGUCUGUUCCCAUAAGUGCAUGAGAAAGAAACACGGGCCUCAUAUAUGAUUGGAUCCUAAAGCCUUCUCACCUACGUGGGGGCUGGCUGUGGCACACGGGGCUCACCCUUUGUGUUUUAGUGGUUCAGAGUGAGCAUUAACAUCAGAUGCUCAUGCGGAGACAGCCAUUACUGUGACUGCCAAGAUGUACUGCAAAAAUACAUGUUCCUGUAUCAGGACUUUGAUUUUGUUAAAAUGGCACUCUCUCCAAAGCUGUGUCCAUGAAGCUGUUUGGAGCUAACGUUGGGUCUUCAUGGUGAUGGACUCAUCCUUAGGCAGCAGUGAUGUCUGCACUAGGAAGAGGCUGGCGGGAGGCGGGGCCCCUCCUGUGCCAGGCACCGAGUGGAUGGGGGACUGAUUAACAUGUUGCUGCCUUCCUCCUCUGUGCAUUGCCUUUUCAUGUCGUCUUCCCAUUUUUACUCUUUUUCUGAUGGAAUUAAUAUUCUUGAUCUGUUAAGGCUAUUAAUCCUUUGUCAUAUAUGUUACAAAUAUUUUCUUUCAAUCUACCAUUUGUCUUAACUCUUUAUUUAGAAUAGUAUCUUUUACGGUGUUUAAUUAUUGUGUAGUAAAAUCUAUCAAUCUUCUCCUUUGUUGAGUGUCUUGGACUUGCUUAAGAAGCCUUUCCCUACUCCAGGGUCAUAAAGUUAAUAGUGUGUGUGUAUGUGUGCGUGUGUGUGUGUGUGUGCGUGCACACGCACACACACACACACACGCUUUUAAUCCAGCUGGGCCUAAUCGUGUGUGUGGUGUGCGUGCUUAGGCAGGAACCCAGUUUUACUUUAUGCCAUGUGGAAAGUUUCUUUUUCCAGUAUCACCAGUGAGUUCACUGUCUCUCCACUGGUCUGCAGUGCUGCUUCUGUUACUUGCAGACUUCCCACGUGUGCAUGGAUCUCCACCUGGGGUCUCUAGGGUCUCUAUUCUACACUGCCUAUUUCCCUUUCUGUCCUAACACCAUAGCAUUUAACUCACCCGUCAUCCUGUGUUGCUGAGAAUUUCCUUCAUAGAACUCAUCAAAGUAUGAUUAACUGUGCUCCCUGAGGGCAGGAAUUAUGCCAUCUGGAUCACCAGCCUCUCCCUUGUCCUUAGCACGCCAUCUGCAAAUUAGCAGAUACUCGGUAAAUGUGUAUUAACUCGAAGUAUAUUUUGUGUCUUCUCUGUGCACAGCACUGCCCUGGGAAGAACUAGGAUGAGGUAUUGACUUGCUGUUGCCACAUAACAAACCCUGCCAGAACUCCCUGGAUGGAAGUGACCACCGUGUAUCUGUGGAUUGUCUGCAGGGCUCUGCUGGGGUCAGCAGGUCCCACAAGAGAGCCAGGGCUCGGUCUCCUCAUGGCUGUCAGAGGUUUACGUAUUCCGCCUCCACCCACCAAAGUCUGAAGUUGUUGUAUUCCAUUCCUUGCUAUAUCCACAUCUUUUAAUAAUGCUAAAAUCCCGUGUUUCUCUAAAGCAUUGGAUUGAACCAACUGAAGAAGGACCACGUGUGUUGCUGGGCCUGCUUGGGCACAAGCCGUUUCCGAUCCAAGUCAACUGCUGGUCUGCUUAGACGAAGGUGUGUGGGUGUCUCCACCACGGAGAGGAGGGACAGCAGGUGAGACCAUAGGCCAGGAAGGAAGGGCACAGCCUAAGCGUGCAGUGGCUUAGCCAGAGACCCUCGUGCACCAGCCUUCAGGUGCUUAUGGAACUUAUGUCAGCCCAGGCCAUAUCCAAGUGUGUGAUGUCUCGGAGCAUAUAUGCCAGGCCAGCCGGAGAGGCUUAGCCCUGCCCUGGUGGAGCUGGAGGGCCGCAGGGCCGCCCGGUGGGGUCAGGAGGUUGUGAAGAGGAUCCUGAUACAGGCUGGGCCUCCCUGCAGGCGUGAGCCCCGGAGCACGGGGUGAGCAGCUCCACCCAGAGGGGCUUGCAGGACCAAGCUGGGACAGCAACCACCAGGCCCUGGGGCAGAUCAGUGAGCGUCCAGGAGAUGCAGAUGCAGAAGACAGCCAAAUUCAUUCACCUCUGCGUGGGCCUGUGAGGGCCCACAGAGAUGCAUUUUCAUUCACGACCAGGAUUUCCUCGGCCGGAGCAGCCGCUUUUCCCAGCCGAAGCUCACUGUGUUUACUACAUAGGAUGUGAGUGUAUAGAAAGACUCUCUCUAACGUUAGCUACGCGUGCAGAAAUGUGGGGCGCUUACAAGUGUGGGCAGCCGCAGCCUGUUCCUCACCCCUGUCCUAACGGGACAUACUCCACGCAUGCACAUUUAGGAUCACCGUGUCUUCUCGUUGGACUGAUCUGUCAUUAGGACCCUGGACCCAAGUAAUUGUCUUUGCUCUGAAGUUUUGACAGUAACAAAGGCAUUCCAGCUCUUUCUUUUUCACUCCUGUCGGUGUAACGUGCCGUUUUUCAUCCUUUGACUUUUAGCCCGCCUGUGCCCUGUCUGAAGGGAGUUGUCUGUGGACAGCACGGAGUGGUGGGUGUUUGUAAUCCACUCUGCCAGCCUCAGUCUUCUAACUGUUGCGUAUGGACCAAUUACAUCUGCCCUUUCUCUUC